ACACACGCAAGCACGCCUCCACUUAACUCGCGCCGCCGCGGCAGCUCGAGUCCACCAGCAGCGCCGUCCGCUUGACCGAGAUGCUGCGGGCCUGUCAGUUAUCGGGUGUGACCGCCGCCGCCCAGAGUUGUCUCUGUGGGAAGUUUGUCCUCCGUCCAUUGCGACCAUGCCGCAGAUACUCUACUUCAGGCAGCUCUGGGUUGACUACUGGCAAAAUUGCUGGAGCUGGCCUUUUGUUUGUUGGUGGAGGUAUUGGUGGCACUAUCCUAUAUGCCAAAUGGGAUUCCCAUUUCCGGGAAAGUGUAGAGAAAACCAUACCUUACUCAGACAAACUCUUCGAGAUGGUUCUUGGUCCUGCAGCUUAUAAUGUUCCAUUGCCAAAGAAAUCGAUUCAGUCGGGUCCACUAAAAAUCUCUAGUGUAUCAGAAGUAAUGAAAGAAUCUAAACAGCCUGCCUCACAACUCCAAAAACAAAAGGGAGAUACUCCAGCUUCAGCAACAGCAGGUGAUACCCUGUCGGUCCCAGCCCCUGCAGUUCAGCCUGAGGAAUCUUUAAAAACUGAUCACCCUGAAAUUGGUGAAGGAAAACCCACACCUGCACUUUCAGAAGCAUCCUCAUCUUCUAUAAGGGAGCGACCACCUGAAGAAGUUGCAGCUCGCCUUGCACAACAGGAAAAACAAGAACAAGUUAAAAUUGAGUCUCUAGCCAAGAGCUUAGAAGAUGCUCUGAGGCAAACUGCAAGUGUCACUCUGCAGGCUAUUGCAGCUCAGAAUGCUGCGGUCCAGGCUGUCAAUGCACACUCCAACAUAUUGAAAGCCGCCAUGGACAAUUCUGAGAUUGCAGGCGAGAAGAAAUCUGCUCAGUGGCGCACAGUGGAGGGUGCAUUGAAGGAACGCAGAAAGGCAGUAGAUGAAGCUGCCGAUGCCCUUCUCAAAGCCAAAGAAGAGUUAGAGAAGAUGAAAAGUGUGAUUGAAAAUGCAAAGAAAAAAGAGGUUGCUGGGGCCAAGCCUCAUAUAACUGCUGCAGAGGGUAAACUUCACAACAUGAUAGUUGAUCUGGAUAAUGUGGUCAAAAAGGUCCAAGCAGCUCAGUCUGAGGCUAAGGUUGUAUCUCAGUAUCAUGAGCUGGUGGUCCAAGCUCGGGAUGACUUUAAACGAGAGCUGGACAGUAUUACUCCAGAAGUCCUUCCUGGGUGGAAAGGAAUGAGUGUUUCAGACUUAGCUGACAAGCUCUCUACUGAUGAUCUGAACUCCCUCAUUGCUCAUGCACAUCGUCGUAUUGAUCAGCUGAACAGAGAGCUGGCAGAACAGAAGGCCACCGAAAAGCAGCACAUCACGUUAGCCUUGGAGAAACAAAAGCUGGAAGAAAAGCGGGCAUUUGACUCUGCAGUAGCAAAAGCAUUAGAACAUCACAGAAGUGAAAUACAGGCUGAACAGGACAGAAAGAUAGAAGAAGUCAGAGAUGCCAUGGAAAAUGAAAUGAGAACCCAGCUUCGCCGACAGGCAGCUGCCCACACUGAUCACUUGCGAGAUGUCCUUAGGGUACAAGAACAGGAAUUGAAGUCUGAAUUUGAGCAGAACCUGUCUGAGAAACUCUCUGAACAAGAAUUACAAUUUCGUCGUCUCAGUCAAGAGCAAGUUGACAACUUUACUCUGGAUAUAAAUACUGCCUAUGCCAGACUCAGAGGAAUCGAACAGGCUGUUCAGAAGUCUUGCUCUGUCGCCCAGGGUAGAGUGCAGUGGUGUGAUAUCGACUCACUGCAGCCUCCGCCUCCUGGGUUCAAGCGAUUCUCCUGCCUCAGACUCCUGAGUAGCUGGGAAUACAGGCCAUGCAGUUGCUGAAGAGGAAGCCAGAAAAGCCCACCAACUCUGGCUUUCAGUGGAGGCAUUAAAGUACAGCAUGAAGACCUCAUCUGCAGAAACACCUACUAUCCCGCUGGGUAGUGCAGUUGAGGCCAUCAAAGCCAACUGUUCUGAUAAUGAAUUCACCCAAGCUUUAACCGCAGCUAUCCCUCCAGAGUCCCUGACCCGUGGGGUGUACAGUGAAGAGACCCUUAGAGCCCGUUUCUAUGCUGUUCAAAAACUGGCCCGAAGGGUAGCAAUGAUUGAUGAAACCAGAAAUAGCUUGUACCAGUACUUCCUCUCCUACCUACAGUCCCUGCUCCUAUUCCCACCUCAGCAACUGAAGCCGCCCCCAGAGCUCUGCCCUGAGGAUAUAAACACAUUUAAAUUACUGUCAUAUGCUUCCUAUUGCAUUGAGCAUGGUGAUCUGGAGCUAGCAGCAAAGUUUGUCAAUCAGCUGAAGGGGGAAUCCAGACGAGUGGCACAGGACUGGCUGAAGGAAGCCCGAAUGACCCUAGAAACGAAACAGAUAGUGGAAAUCCUGACAGCAUAUGCCAGCGCCGUAGGAAUAGGAACCACUCAGGUGCAGCCAGAGUGAGGUUUAGGAAGAUUUUCAUAAAGUCAUAUUUCAUGUCAAAGGAAAUCAGCAGUGAUAGAUGAAGGGUUCGCAGCGAGAGUCCCGGACUUGUCUAGAAAUGAGCAGGUUUACAAGUACUGUUCUAAAUGUUAACACCUGUUGCAUUUAUAUUCUUUCCAUUUGCUAUCAUGUCAGUGAACGCCAGGAGUGCUUUCUUUGCAACUUGUGUAACAUUUUCUGUUUUUUCAGGUUUUACUGAUGAGGCUUGUGAGGCCAAUCAAAAUAAUGUUUGUGAUCUCUACUACUGUUGAUUUUGCCCUCGGAGCAAACUGAAUAAAGCAACAAGAUGAAAA